GCCCACACAGCAGGGGGCUGGCUUGGGCUGGCAGGGUGCUUGCCUGGGGAGGCUGGUGAGUUUGUUUUUGACUCGAUGAGCCUAGACCAGAGUCCUGGGUGCUCUACUCAGGGAGAAGAACGACCAUCAGACGAGAAGCUGGCUUGUAUAGGAAGCUGUGUACCAUUUUCAGGAAGUGUAGAAGCUCAUUUGGGUGAUUUCCUGGGGUCACUUGGCCAGAGCACAGCCCUUUAUCUUACCCAGUUAGCAGUUUGCUGUCUUAAUUAUUGGGGAGAUGUGUGUGAUUGCUGGUGUAUCCUCAUGUCCUGCUCCCUAAUUAUGACUUUCUUUAAGAUUUUACACUGAUAAGGCACUUUAAAGUUCUUCAGAGCCUUUUCCCUAUAUUAUAUCUUAUUUUAUUCUCAAACUCAUUCUUUUAAAUAGAUGGGAUAAUUUUUUCAUUUUUUAUCUUUAUUUUGGAAACAUCCUUUUUCCUCCUCCAUAAUACCUGAGCCUUGUCCCACCCUUGCCAAAUAAUCCCAGAGAAAUGGGAAGUCCUCUCUAUCCUAUCCUAGAGGUCUGACAUAACAAUUAAAUGUAUAUAUUCCCAGACAGACUUUUCUUUUUUCUUUUUUUUUUGAAAACCACUAACUUUAUUGAUCUAAAAAACUUUACAAGGACAGUGACUGUUCUGCCAAAAAAGGAGCCAAAUGGUAUCAAAUGGACUGCAAGUGAGGGUGGGGGUGAGAGACGGGGCCAGGAAUCCAUGCAGGAAAGCUGAUAACUGUCACCAGGGAAUUGGCAAGGGAAAAAGGAAGGAGGAGGCAUACAAGAGCGAGAAUCCAAAAAAGUUGAAAUGGUUAGGGGAGAAAACUCUCAAAAGACCCUGGAGUACAUCAGAGACAUUCACGGCAUGGUGUAACUCCCACCUCCGGAAGGCGGGGACACAGAUCGAGAACAUCGAAGAGGACUUCCGGGAUGGCCUGAAGCUCAUGCUGCUGCUGGAGGUCAUCUCAGGUGAACGCUUGGCCAAGCCAGAGCGAGGCAAGAUGAGAGUGCACAAGAUCUCCAACGUCAACAAGGCCCUGGAUUUCAUAGCCAGCAAAGGCGUCAAACUGGUGUCCAUCGGAGCCGAAGAAAUCGUGGAUGGGAAUGUGAAGAUGACCCUGGGCAUGAUCUGGACCAUCAUCCUGCGCUUUGCCAUCCAGGACAUCUCCGUGGAAGAGACUUCAGCCAAGGAAGGGCUGCUCCUGUGGUGUCAGAGAAAGACAGCCCCUUACAAAAAUGUCAACAUCCAGAACUUCCACAUAAGCUGGAAGGAUGGCCUCGGCUUCUGUGCUUUGAUCCACCGACACCGGCCCGAGCUGAUUGACUACGGGAAGCUGCGGAAGGAUGAUCCACUCACAAAUCUGAAUACGGCUUUUGACGUGGCAGAGAAGUACCUGGACAUCCCCAAGAUGCUGGAUGCCGAAGACAUCGUUGGAACUGCCCGACCGGAUGAGAAAGCCAUCAUGACUUACGUGUCUAGCUUCUACCACGCCUUCUCUGGAGCCCAGAAGGCGGAGACAGCAGCCAAUCGCAUCUGCAAGGUGUUGGCCGUCAACCAGGAGAACGAGCAGCUUAUGGAAGACUACGAGAAGCUGGCCAGUGAUCUGUUGGAGUGGAUCCGCCGCACAAUCCCGUGGCUGGAGAACCGGGUGCCCGAGAACACCAUGCAUGCCAUGCAACAGAAGCUGGAGGACUUCCGGGACUACCGGCGCCUGCACAAGCCGCCCAAGGUGCAGGAGAAGUGCCAGCUGGAGAUCAACUUCAACACGCUGCAGACCAAGCUGCGGCUCAGCAACCGGCCUGCCUUCAUGCCCUCUGAGGGCAGGAUGGUCUCGGACAUCAACAAUGCCUGGGGCUGCCUGGAGCAGGUGGAGAAGGGCUAUGAGGAGUGGUUGCUGAAUGAGAUCCGGAGGCUGGAGCGACUGGACCACCUGGCAGAGAAGUUCCGGCAGAAGGCCUCCAUCCACGAGGCCUGGACUGACGCCAUGUGGCCCUCUCUCAACCCAGGCAAAGAGGCCAUGCUGCGACAGAAGGACUAUGAGACCGCCACCCUCUCGGAGAUCAAGGCCCUGCUCAAGAAGCAUGAGGCCUUCGAGAGUGACCUGGCUGCCCACCAGGACCGUGUGGAGCAGAUUGCCGCCAUCGCACAGGAGCUCAAUGAGCUGGACUAUUAUGACUCACCCAGUGUCAACGCCCGUUGCCAAAAGAUCUGUGACCAGUGGGACAAUCUGGGGGCCCUAACUCAGAAGCGAAGGGAAGCUCUGGAGCGGACCGAGAAACUGCUGGAGACCAUUGACCAGCUGUACUUGGAGUAUGCCAAGCGGGCUGCACCCUUCAACAACUGGAUGGAGGGGGCCAUGGAGGACCUGCAGGACACCUUCAUUGUGCACACCAUUGAGGAGAUCCAGGGACUGACCACAGCCCAUGAGCAGUUCAAGGCCACCCUCCCUGAUGCCGACAAGGAGCGCCUGGCCAUCCUGGGCAUCCACAAUGAGGUGUCCAAGAUUGUCCAGACCUACCACGUCAAUAUGGCGGGCACCAACCCCUACACAACCAUCACGCCUCAGGAGAUCAAUGGCAAAUGGGACCACGUGCGGCAGCUGGUGCCUCGGAGGGACCAAGCUCUGACGGAGGAGCAUGCCCGACAGCAGCACAAUGAGAGGCUACGCAAGCAGUUUGGAGCCCAGGCCAAUGUCAUCGGGCCCUGGAUCCAGACCAAGAUGGAGGAGAUCGGGAGGAUCUCCAUUGAGAUGCAUGGGACCCUGGAGGACCAGCUCAGCCACCUGCGGCAGUAUGAGAAGAGCAUCGUCAACUACAAGCCAAAGAUUGAUCAGCUGGAGGGCGACCACCAGCUCAUCCAGGAGGCGCUCAUCUUCGACAACAAGCACACCAACUACACCAUGGAGCACAUCCGUGUGGGCUGGGAGCAGCUGCUCACCACCAUCGCCAGGACCAUCAAUGAGGUAGAGAACCAGAUCCUGACCCGGGAUGCCAAGGGCAUCAGCCAGGAGCAGAUGAAUGAGUUCCGGGCCUCCUUCAACCACUUUGACCGGGAUCACUCCGGCACACUGGGUCCCGAGGAGUUCAAAGCCUGCCUCAUCAGCUUGGGUUAUGAUAUUGGCAACGACCCCCAGGUACUCGCCUCCUGCAUGGAGCACGCUCAGGGGUGGCGUCUGGGGCAAGAAAUAAUGCGUUUUUCCUUUUUCUCUUCUCUCUGUCUGGAUCUCCUGUCCCCCUCCUGUGGGCCAUGGGGCUCGUCCUCUCCUGCUGUCUCUGUCUGCCCCAUCACUGGUCCACCCUCUGCCCUCUGCUGUCUUUCAUGGCAACCUACUGGGUGCCCGCUGUCUUCCGUCCUCGCUGCUCUUCAUCCCAUGGGUGGAUUUUUGCAUCUCCCUGCUCUGUCUUCCUCCUGUCUUUGGACAUUUCCACCGAUGUGUGUUCGCAUCUUCUCCUAUGUUCCUUUACCUAUCCUGACCCCCAAAACCAUAAAUCUCAUCCCCGUUCUGGCCAUCUGUUCCUGUCUUCCUGGCCCCGGGCCGGCCCUUCCUCUUCCUGCCUUCCCGACCCUCCUUGUGUCUUGGUACCACUGCCCCCCACAGAAGAAGACAGGCAUGAUGGACACGGAUGAUUUCCGCGCCUGCCUGAUCUCCAUGGGUUACAACAUGGGAGAAGCAGAAUUUGCCCGCAUCAUGAGCAUUGUGGACCCCAACCGCCUGGGGGUAGUGACAUUCCAGGCCUUCAUUGACUUCAUGUCCCGCGAGACAGCCGACACAGAUACAGCAGACCAAGUCAUGGCUUCCUUCAAGAUCCUGGCUGGGGACAAGAACUACAUUACCAUGGACGAGCUGCGCCGCGAGCUGCCACCCGACCAGGCUGAGUACUGCAUCGCGCGGAUGGCCCCCUACACCGGCCCCGACUCCGUGCCAGGUGCUCUGGACUACAUGUCCUUCUCCACGGCGCUGUACGGCGAGAGUGACCUCUAAUCCACCCCGCCCGGCCGCCCUCGUCUUGUGCGCCGUGCCCUGCCUUGCACCUCCGCCGUCGCCCAUCUCCUGCCUGGGUUCGGUUUCAGCUCCCAGCCUCCACCCGGGUGAGCUGGGGCCCACGUGGCAUCGAUCCUCCCUGCCCGCGAAGUGACAGUUUACAAAAUUAUUUUCUGCAAAAAAGAAAAAAAAGUUACGUUAAAAACCAAAAAACUACAUAUUUUAUUAUAGAAAAAGUAUUUUUUCUCCACCAGACAAAUGGAAAAAAAGAGGAAAGAUUAACUAUUUGCACCGAAAUGUCUUGUUUUGUUGCGACAUAGGAAAAUAACCAAGCACAAAGUUAUAUUCCAUCCUUUUUACUGAUUUUUUUUUCUUCUAUCUGUUCCAUCUGCUGUAUUCAUUUCUCCAAUCUCAUGUCCAUUUUGGUGUGGGAGUCGGGGUAGGGGGUACUCUUGUCAAAAGGCACAUUGGUGCAUGUGUGUUUGCUAGCUCACUUGUCCAUGAAAAUAUUUUAUGAUAUUAAAGAAAAUCUUUUGAAAUGGCUGUUUUUUAAGGAAGAGAAUUUAUGUGGCUUCUCAUUUUUAAAUCCCCUCAGAGGUGUGACUAGUCUCUUUAUCAGCACACACUUAAAAAAUUUUUAAUAUUGUCUAUUAAAAAUAGGACAAACUUGGAGAGUAUGGACAACUUUGAUAUUGCUUGGCACAGAUGGUAUUAAAAAAACCACACUCCUA